GACUCGCGUUGGUGCCGGCCGCCUCCCGCGCCUAGUGUCCGGGACGCGCCUGAACCUGCCGCCUCCGUGCCUGGGGCGGCGCCGCGCGGCCCCCAGGCUCCCGCGGGGCCGACCUCGGAGACGCAGCUGGGGCCGGGCGCGGCUUGGCGGGAGGGUCUGCAGCGCCGAGGGAGGCUGCCAGUGCGUGAGGAAGAGAGCUAGAGACUGGACAGGGGAGACAGAGCAGCGUCGGAGCCGCGCAGGGGACGGGAGUGAGAGCGGGAGUGAGAGCAGGAACGACGCAGAGCGGCCGUCGCCGUGCCCGGGUCUCAGGGCGCCUGGCUGAAGUGAGCAUGGCUUCAGUGGCCUGGGCCGUCCUCAAGGUGCUGCUGCUUCUCCCCACUCAGACUUGGAGCCCCGUAGGAGCAGGAAAUCCACCUGACUGUGAUUCCCCACUGGCCUCUGCCUUGCCUAGGUCAUCCUUCAGCAGCUCCUCAGAGCUGUCCAGCAGCCACGGCCCGGGGUUUUCAAGGCUUAAUCGAAGAGAUGGAGCUGGUGGCUGGACCCCACUUGUGUCAAAUAAAUACCAAUGGCUGCAAAUUGACCUUGGAGAGAGAAUGGAGGUCACUGCUGUCGCCACCCAAGGAGGAUAUGGGAGCUCUGACUGGGUGACCAGCUACCUCCUGAUGUUCAGUGAUGGUGGGAGAAACUGGAAGCAGUAUCGCCGAGAAGAAAGCAUCUGGGGUUUUCCAGGAAACACAAACGCAGACAGUGUGGUGCACUACAGACUCCAGCCUCCCUUUGAAGCCAGGUUCCUGCGCUUUCUCCCUUUAGCCUGGAACCCCAGGGGCAGGAUUGGGAUGCGGAUCGAAGUGUACGGAUGUGCAUAUAAAUCUGAGGUGGUUUAUUUUGAUGGACAAAGUGCUCUGCUGUAUACACUUGAUAAAAAACCUUUAAAACCAAUAAGAGAUGUUAUUUCUUUGAAAUUUAAAGCCAUGCAGAGCAAUGGAAUUCUACUUCACAGAGAAGGACAACAUGGAAAUCACAUUACUCUGGAAUUAAUUAAAGGAAAGCUUGUCUUUUUUCUUAAUUCAGGCAAUGCUAAGCUGCCUUCUACUAUUGCUCCUGUGACCCUCACCCUGGGCAGCCUGCUGGAUGACCAGCACUGGCAUUCCGUCCUCAUCGAGCUCCUCGACACGCAGGUCAACUUCACCGUGGACAAACACACUCAUCAUUUCCAAGCAAAGGGAGAUUCCAGUAACUUGGAUCUUAAUUUUGAGAUCAGCUUUGGGGGAAUUCUGUCACCCGGAAGAUCACGGGCAUUCACACGUAAAAGCUUUCAUGGGUGUUUAGAAAAUCUUUAUUAUAAUGGAGUGGAUGUUACCGAAUUAGCCAAGAAACACAAACCACAGAUCCUCAUGAUGGGAAAUGUGUCCUUCUCAUGUCCACAGCCACAGACUGUCCCUGUGACUUUUCUGAGCUCCAGGAGUUAUCUGGCUCUGCCAGGCAACUCUGGGGAGGACAAAGUGUCUGUCACUUUUCAAUUUCGAACGUGGAACAGAGCAGGACAUUUGCUUUUCGGCGAACUUCAACGUGGUUCAGGGAGUUUCGUCCUCUUUCUUAAGGAUGGCAAGCUCAAACUGAGUCUCUUCCAGGCGGGACAGUCACCAAGGAAUGUCACAGCAGGUGCUGGAUUAAACGAUGGGCAGUGGCACUCUGUAUCCUUCUCUGCCAAGUGGAGCCAUAUGAAUGUGGUGGUGGAUGAUGACACAGCUGUUCAGCCCCUGGUGGCUGUGCUCAUUGAUUCAGGUGACACCUAUUAUUUUGGAGGCUGCCUGGGCAACAGCUCUGGCUCUGGAUGUAAAAGCCCCCUGGGAGGGUUUCAGGGCUGCCUAAGGCUCAUCACCAUUGGUGACAAAGCGGUGGAUCCCAUCUUAGUACAGCAGGGGGCGCUGGGGAGUUUCAGGGACCUCCAGAUAGACUCCUGCGGCAUCACAGACAGGUGCUUGCCCAGCUACUGUGAGCAUGGGGGCGAGUGUUCCCAGUCGUGGGACACCUUCUCCUGUGACUGUCUAGGCACAGGCUAUACGGGCGAGACCUGCCAUUCCUCUCUCUACGAGCAGUCUUGUGAAGCCCACAAGCACCGAGGGAACCCAUCCGGGCUUUACUAUAUUGAUGCAGAUGGAAGUGGCCCCCUGGGACCAUUUCUUGUGUACUGCAAUAUGACAGCAGACUCCGCGUGGACGGUGGUGCGGCACGGUGGCCCCGACGCGGUGACCCUCCGAGGUGCCCCCAGCGGGCACCCGCUCUCGGCUGUGUCCUUCGCGUACGCAGCGGGCGCGGGGCAGCUGCGGGCCGCGGUGAACCUGGCGGAGCGCUGCGAGCAGCGGCUGGCUCUGCGCUGCGGGACAGCGCGGCGCCCGGACUCACGAGAUGGAACCCCACUGAGCUGGUGGGUUGGAAGAACCAAUGAAACACACACUUCCUGGGGAGGUUCUCUGCCUGAUGCUCAAAAGUGUACUUGUGGAUUAGAGGGGAACUGCAUUGAUUCUCAGUAUUACUGCAACUGUGAUGCUGGCCAGAAUGAAUGGACUAGUGACACAAUAGUCCUUUCCCAAAAGGAGCACCUCCCAGUCACUCAGAUUGUGAUGACAGACACAGGCCAACCACAUUCCGAAGCAGAUUAUACACUGGGGCCACUGCUCUGCCGCGGAGAUAAGUCAUUUUGGAAUUCAGCUUCCUUCAACACUGAGACUUCAUACCUUCAUUUCCCUGCUUUCCACGGAGAACUCACUGCUGACGUGUGCUUCUUUUUUAAGACCACAGUUUCCUCUGGGGUGUUUAUGGAGAACCUGGGGAUCACAGACUUCAUCAGGAUUGAGCUGCGGGCUCCCACAGAAGUGACAUUUUCCUUCGAUGUGGGGAAUGGACCUUGUGAGGUCACGGUGCAGUCACCCACUCCCUUUAAUGACAAUCAGUGGCACCACGUGAGGGCAGAGAGAAAUGUUAAAGGAGCGUCUCUUCAAGUUGAUCAGCUUCCUCAGAAGAUGCAGCCUGCCCCUGCUGAUGGGCACGUUCGUUUACAGCUCAACAGCCAGCUCUUCAUUGGUGGAACGGCCACCAGACAGAGAGGCUUUCUAGGAUGCAUUCGGUCUCUGCAGUUGAACGGGGUGGCCCUGGAUCUGGAAGAAAGAGCCACAGUGACGCCAGGAGUGGAGCCAGGGUGUGCAGGACACUGCAGCACCUAUGGACACUUGUGUCGCAAUGGAGGGAGAUGCAGAGAGAAACGCAGGGGGGUCACCUGUGACUGUGCCUUCUCAGCCUAUGAUGGACCGUUCUGCUCCAAUGAGAUUUCCGCAUAUUUCGCAACUGGCUCCUCAAUGACAUACCAUUUUCAAGAACAUUACACUUUAAGUGAAAACUCCAGCUCUCUCGUUUCUUCAUUACACAGAGAUGUAACAUUGACCAGAGAAAUGAUCACACUGAGCUUCCGAACCACACGAACUCCGAGCUUAUUGCUGUAUGUGAGCUCUUUCUAUGAGGAAUACCUUUCAGUUAUCCUCGCCAACAAUGGAAGUUUGCAGAUUAGGUACAAGCUAGAUAGACAUCAAAAUCCUGAUGCAUUUACCUUUGAUUUUAAAAACAUGGCUGAUGGGCAACUUCACCAAGUGAAGAUUAACAGAGAAGAAGCCGUGGUCAUGGUAGAGGUUAACCAGAGCGCAAAGAAACAAGUCAUCUUGUCCUCAGGGACAGAAUUCAACGCCGUCAAAUCUCUCAUAUUGGGAAAGGUUUUAGAGGCUGCCGGCGCGGACCCGGACACAAGGCGGGCGGCGACUAGUGGCUUCACUGGCUGCCUCUCGGCGGUGCGCUUCGGCUGCGCUGCUCCCCUGAAGGCGGCGCUGCGCCCCAGCGGCCCCUCCCGGGUCACCGUCCGCGGCCACGUGGCCCCUAUGGCCCGCUGCGCGGCGGGGGCGGCGUCCGGCUCCCCGGCGCGGGAACUGGCUCCCCGACUCGCGGGGGGCGCAGGUCGUUCUGGACCAGUGGAUGAGGGAGAGCCCUUGGUUAAUGCAGACAGAAGAGACUCUGCUGUCAUCGGAGGUGUGAUAGCAGUGGAGAUAUUUAUUUUGCUUUGCAUCACUGCCAUAGCCAUACGCAUCUAUCAACAGAGAAAGUUACGCAAAGAAAAUGAGUCAAAAGUCUCAAAAAAAGAAGAGUGCUAGGACAGCUCUAAACAGUGAGCUCGAUGUGCAAAACGCAGUCCAUGAAAACCAGAAAGAGUGAGUCUUCUGAUUGGCAGCUGUGGCUGUCUCUAUCAUCGUGACUGUGGACUUCCCUGCUGUUGCCAUCAGGGUGCACACAGCAGGUGCAGUGCUGUCACCUGGCUGAAGAUCUGCAGCCUCAGAGCCUCUGGGAGGUCCCUUUCUCCCUCGGUGAAACACAGUCCUCCACAUCAAUUUCCAAACAAUGAAUUAGGUAUGGCCAUUCAUCACUGUUCAGUAGUUUCCCCGUCCAAAGGCUCUCUUCCAAAACUGCAGUUUGAUCUGUGUUAAUAAUUGUGGGGUUUUAGAUGAGAAAAUGACUAUAAAGCUGUGGCCCUACUUUAUUUUUUAAAAAUGACAGAACUUUUGUUCAGAUGUAAAAGACAAAAUUGCACUUUAAUGUUUUUUGUUACUUGAAAACAUAUCUGGGAUCCCUUUUUUUGGUCCUCUGCUGAUAUUAUAAAACAAGAAAUGCUUCUUGGACUACCUUCACUGGCAUUUCCAUAGUCCUGGAAUCCAGAGCCAAGUGGCCUAUCUAAAAUUCACAGCCCUUUUAUUCUCCUGUGUGAUGGUUAAUACAACACAGUUGAAGCCUGGAAACACUACCAUUAUUUUUGGUGUAUUGCUUUUUCUAAUUGACUGUUUUUAAUGAUUUUGAUACAUUUUAAUGUUGAAAUUAAUAUUGAAUGUUAGCUAUGAAAUUUUAGUAUUGAAUUUUAUAAUGGAACAGAACAUUGGUAGGUAACAAGAUGCAAGAGGAUGUCAAUACAAGAUUGUCUGCCUGUUUUUCUUUGUAAUUUGUAAUUACAGUUUUUGUAACUUGUGAUUAUGUUUUUAACUAAAUUUACCACCAGAUACAAACACUACUUCUUACACAGAGUUAUCCUUUAUUUAUAUCAUUAAGACGUGAAUGAAACAUCAUCCUAACUUACUUCCCCAAGAUAUUGAGAGGUCAUAUCUGUUUUUCAUCAUUCAUUUCUUUUUCUAAAAGUUGUUACUGAUAUGCUUUUGAUUUCCUAUGACUCUAUUAUGUUGUACAGAACAUCUUUUCAAUUUAUUAAAAAAAAUAGCUUAACUGAAGAUCACUAAUUCCUUUUCUAAAUUUUGAACUGCUCUAGGCAUAAAUAUCAUUGUGUAUUAUCCUUUCAUCUAAUCACUUUUGGAAUGUAAACUGAAGGCUGUUCACUCCAAGUUAAGUUAACAUUUACAUGAUGUUUAUUAAAUCUGCCAGUCUGAUCAAAGGUUUAUGACCAUGGGGCCAAAUUCCCAUAGAUUACCCAAAAUUGAAUAUGUGCAGUUAACUGGAACAUGUCUCAUUAAGGUUUACAUACACACUAAGACAGCAAAGGAUUGGAAUUAACUUUAUGGAGACAGUUCCAGGGACUAAUAUUGAAGCAGUGGUUAUUUGAUAAUGCAUGGAACCACCAUUUGGAUUCAAUAAACCAAUUACAUAAAAGCAAUGAUGCUACGCUCUUCAUAUUCCAGAUACCAACUGCCUACCAAGGACUAAUGAGAUGGUAUAUUUCUUCCACAUCAGGGCAAGCUGAAAAUAUAUUGAUUCAGCGUUACUGUUAUGUAAAUGAAUUUCCAUCUUCUCAUAUGUGUUAUUUUUGAAAGAAUGAAUACACUCUCUGUCUUAAAUCCGCUCUUAACAAAUGAUCUCUUCUCAGAAUACUACAUCUGUAUUGAGAGUACAGACAGCCCAUUGGUCACUGCACCUUUUGCAAGACAGCGAAACGGAUGCAUCAAAUUGCAUUGAUACAUCAUCACCAUCAAUCUUUUGCACUGAUUUUUAGACUUAAUCUUCUUAUUUGAAAAUAAACUCAUUUUUAAAUAAAAUAAAAAAUAUUUUAGGGAAAGCUCUAUAAAAUUAAAAUUACAGAAUUAUAUGCUUUUUAAAAUUUAUGCAAAAAUGUGCAGACAAAUGUAUUCUGUAUUGGUUUAUGUAUCACUUUGCCCUUGUAUAUUUUGAGAUUAUUAAGAUUUGUUGACUUUUUUGGUUUGAUAUUUAUCAUCUGUUAAAUUUUUCCUUUUAAAUUAUUAAAUGCAAAGUGCAAGAAAAAGAGAUAAAUAUUUACUGAUUGCUAGAUGUAAAAAUAUCUAUGAAUAUAUAUAUUUAAACUUCUGCCAGAGAGCAACCAUCUGACAGUCAACUUACUAAAAUCUAAAUUGAGUACUUUUUACUGUUGCAGAGAAUUAAGUCACUAAACGUUAUUUAGAUAUAUAGAUGCUAGUUGCAAGUAACACCCUUUUGUAAUAUAAAAGUAAAAGCAUAAUAAUUUCCCAACUUUUGUCUUCAAAUUAAAAAAGAAAAUAGCAUAUAAUUACCAUUCUUCAUUUGAGAAAGCUGAAGAUUCUGAUGCUUAAAAACUUCAGAAUUCUAAUAUUAAAAAUAGAGUGGUUCAUGUGACAUUGAAGGCUUAUCUCUGUAAAAUAGUGACACUGGUGAGUGGUAUUAUCUCAAUAUUUUUGUCCAAAUUCACCUUAGGAAGUCACUGUAAAUCUUCAUUGUUUCCUAAAAGUCAUUAUUACGGCAUAAACUUAACAUACUUUGAUAGUAGUUAGUACUGAUACGUGACAUAUUCUACCCCGUGUCUCUGUUACUCUGUCUCUAUUACUGUGAAAAGUCACAGUAAAUUUAACAUUUUCUUCCAGACUGUGUAUGAUCUUUCAUUGUAAUAGAGACAUGGAGUAGGAUAAGUCAUGUAUUAACAUAUAAGAUUUUUUUAACCUGCUCCCUCAGUUUUAUAGAUGAGACAAAGAUAAGGUUGUAAGAGCUAAUCUCUUCAAGUAGGCAGUACUAGUAAGUUGUCAUGCGUGGACUGAACUCCUGGCACUUCUUUCUCUUAACUUCAAUCCAUAGAGAAGCCCACCUUCCUGCCUUCCCAGUAUUAUUUAGCAGAGGAGAAAAUCAUAUUAGGCUGUUUGAUACUCUGUUUGCCUAGACUGAUCAAUAAUUCUGGAUCUUUGUUCACAUCUUCUCUGAAAGAAUAUUUGAUGGGAAAUCUUUUUUAUUUUUUAAUUUUUGUGUACAUACUAGGUGCAUAUAUUUAUGGAGUACAUGAAAUGUUUUGAUACAGGCAUGCACUGUGAAAUAAGCACAUCAUGGAGAAUGGGGUAUCCAUCCCCUCAACAUUUAUCCUUUGUGUUACAAACAACCUGAUUACACUCUGUAUUUUAAAAUAUGCAGUUAAGUUUUUAUUGACUAUAGUCACCCUAUUGUGCUAUCAUAUAGUAAGUUUUACUCAUUCUUUCUACUUUUUUUGUACCCAUUAACCUAUCCCCACCUCUGCCCCACCAUUAUCUCAGCUGUCUACUACUUUUUUCAGCCUUUACUAACCAUCCUUCUACUCUAUAUCCAUGAGUUCCGUUGUUUUGGUUUUUAGAUCCCACAAAUAAAUGAGAACAUGGCAA